AUCUGAGACGCACGCGAUGCUGGCGACGCUGGCGAGGGUGGCAGCUCUGCGCAGAACCUGCCUCUUCUCCGGCCGGGGCGGCGGGAGGGGGCUGUGGACUGGCCGCCCGCAGUCAGAUAUGAACAAUAUAAAGCCAUUGGAAGGGGUAAAAAUUCUGGAUCUAACAAGAGUCCUGGCGGGACCUUUUGCUACUAUGAAUUUAGGAGAUCUUGGAGCAGAAGUUAUAAAAGUGGAGAGACCAGGAGCUGGUGAUGAUACACGAACUUGGGGGCCACCUUUUGUUGGGACAGAAAGUACAUAUUAUCUCAGUGUUAACCGAAAUAAAAAAAGUAUUGCUGUUAAUAUCAAGGAUCCAAAAGGGGUGAAAAUCAUCAAAGAGCUUGCAGCUGUUUGUGAUGUGUUUGUGGAAAACUAUGUCCCUGGCAAACUGUCUGCAAUGGGCCUGGGAUAUGAAGAUAUAGACGAGAUUGCUCCUCACAUCAUCUAUUGUUCCAUCACAGGGUAUGGUCAGACAGGUCCAAUUUCUCAGCGAGCUGGUUAUGAUGCUGUUGCCUCGGCUGUUUCUGGUCUGAUGCACAUCACAGGGCCUGAGAAUGGAGAUCCAGUUCGCCCAGGAGUAGCUAUGACUGAUCUUGCCACUGGCCUGUAUGCAUAUGGAGCUAUUAUGGCUGGAUUGAUACAAAAAUACAAAACUGGGAAAGGACUGUUCAUUGAUUGUAACCUACUGUCAUCCCAGGUGGCGUGUUUGUCUCACAUAGCUGCAAAUUAUCUUAUUGGUCAAAAGGAAGCAAAACGUUGGGGUACAGCUCAUGGCAGUAUCGUUCCUUACCAGGCUUUUAAAACCAAGGAUGGCUAUAUUGUAGUUGGAGCAGGAAAUAACCAGCAGUUUGCCACCGUCUGCAAGAUCUUGGAUUUGCCUGAGUUGAUUGAUAAUUCCAAGUAUAAAACUAACCACCUUCGGGUACACAAUAGAAAAGAGCUUAUUAAAAUAUUAUCUGAACGGUUUGAAGAAGAACUGACCAGCAAGUGGUUAUAUCUUUUUGAAGGCAGUGGAGUCCCGUAUGGCCCAAUCAACAACAUGAAGAAUGUAUUUGCAGAACCUCAGUCACUGAACAGACAUGAAUGGGCACCGACUAUGUACCUGCCAUUGUGUAGGGCUGUAGAGAGCAGUCAGAAAUGGAGGAGAAAAGAGAAUACCUACAAUCUUGAGAAACUCCGUCCAGAGGAGAACUUAAAAAACACACUAAUAAAGGAAGAUAUUAAUUGCGAGGGAAACACAGAGAUGGGAAUAACAACACUAUGAAGGGGUAGGAGUUAGGAUCUGCUCUGCAGGCUGGUGAGAGGUAAGUAUUAAAAGAUAUUUGUAUGUUUGAAAGAUACUUGUAUGUUUGCCAGUAAGACAAGUUUGGGCGUGGCAGAUAGUAGAUGGUAGAAGAAAUGGUGUGUGUGUGUCUCACAGGGCCUUUUGAGAGGCUGGAGUCCAAGGAGUGGAGCUUGGUGAGAGGUGGGCUAGAGUGGUAGGUUACAAUCAGUUUGUGCAGUGCCUUGUCUAGCAUGCUGAGCAGAUUGCAUCGUAUUCAGUCGGAGAAGGCAAGUCGUUGAACGACUGUCACUAGGAGAGUGUGAGGGCUGCUUUUCAUUUUAGAAACAUCUCUCAGGAAGGUAGUGGAUGGAUAGAGGGUAGAGGAAUGUCAAAAAUAGCAACAGGAAGCUGUCUACCUUCUGUUGGAGCAGAAAAGACAAAAGAAGAAGGACAAAGAGAGUGGGGCUCCUGGAGAAAGGAUUAACGGGAAAGCUUUCUAAGAGGCAGAAAGUUGAUUGAAGGUGGAGGAUGACAAAGAAGGAAGCAUUGAAGAAGACUGAAAGUGUGGAUGACACUGAUAACAGGAUGAGCUGAGAAAGGUUUGGUGCUGCAGUCGUGAGUUUCACUUUGGGCAUAUGGAAACUGAAGCGACCACGUGUGAGGAUACCCACUACACAGAUGGAAACAGGGUCUUCAGCUCAGAGAGAGAAAAUGCAAAAGGGCGAGAUUUGGGAUCCUAGAGCAUCCAGGAAGCGUCUUUGUGUGGAAUACAGGGGAAUAGAGGCAAAUGGAGCCUUUCCUUGUUUCCUGCUUCCCUUUUACUUAGGAGAUUAAAGUGACAGUUUCAUUAACUGCUUUUACCACAUUAAACAUUGUUGAGGAUUUGGAUUUGGGUAACAUUUUGUCUUAAUAAGAAACCUACUAAAAAGUAAGUUUUUCAAAAAAUGUUUUACUCUUACAUGAUCAAGUCUUUAUCAUGGAACCUGUCAGCGUUAACAUCUAGGAUUUAAUGUCAACCAACGUAAGCUUUUAAAAAGCCAUAUUAAAUCAGAAAUGACUUAAAAAUAAACUCUAGAUGAACUUGAUCUAUUUAAGUUAAAGGAUUAAGUUAUAUACAUGAUGGAGCAUCAGAGAUUGAGUCCUUUUUGGGUGGGCCUUGGAAAGGGAAAAUGCAGAAAGUUCUAAUUUGUUUUGCUUUCGAAGAAGAAUCAUCCUUUUUAUGUAUUCAUAUGCAUAAUUUGAUCAGAAAAAUGCUUGAUAUUCUAACCUUUUAAUUAGGAGGGAGGAAUGUAGAGAUCAUGUUGUAAAAUUGUUUUCCAGGUGAGGAAUCUGUGCAAUAAAUUUGAGAAACACUGAAGGCUUUAUUGUAUGCUUUUUCUGGAUUUUUUUUUUUUUUUUGAGACAGAGUGUCACUUUGUCAGCCAGGCUGGAGUGCAGUGAUACAAUUAUAGCUCACUACAGCCUCAACCUCUGGGCUCAAGUUAUCCUCCCACCUCAGCCCCCCAAGUAGCUGGAACUAUAGGAAUGCACCACCACACUCAGCUAAUUUUUAAAUUUUUUGUAGAGACAGGGUCUCACUAUAUUGCCCAGGCUGGUCUCAAACUCCUGGGCUUAAGUGCUUCUCUCACCUAGGCCUCCCAAGUGCUGGGAUUACAGGUGUGAGCCAUCACACCUGGCUGAAUUUUAUAAUUUACCUUGUGACAUUGAAGACUCUGAGAAGUUCUGCAGGAACCUAGCGUUUCCCAGUCUUAUUUGAUGGCCAACCCAGUAUUUCCCAGAGUUUGGAUGAUGUUACUUUAAAAGUUACCUUUAUAAUUAAGUAGAGCAAUGUAAGUGUUCAAGCUUUUAGCCACAGAGCUCAGUUCAAUUAGUAAACAUGUAUUGAGCUCUUUUAUCAUAGUUACCCUGUUAAGUCCCCAAAUCAUGAAGAUUAUUCAUAAAACAAUAAUAAUGACAACAAUAAUAGUAGCUAAGACUUGUUGAGUGCAUACUAGGUGCCAGGAAAUUUACUAAGCAUGUUGCAUACACCAUCUCAUUUAAUCCUCACAACUCUGGGAGAAAAGUAUCCAUUUUAGAAAAGAGGAAAUUCAGACCCAGAGAGGUGAAGUGCUUUUCCUAAGGCCAUAGACCUAGUGAAUUACAGAACUGGGUUUUAGACAUGUUUCUACCUGAUACUGCUGCUCACAUUCUUAACUACCAUAGCCCUGUCUAUGGAGAAUUUAUGGCCUCAAUAAUGUCCAUGAAUAUUUCCAAGAUGGGCUUCAGGUAUUUUGACUUGAGGGUCUUCAACCUGUGAGUUCUAUUAUUAGUUUCUGAUAUUCUGCAUUACCCUGAAACGUCUUCCUAAUUUAGAACCAAGGUAGCCCCUUUCUCUCUGAAUCUGAAGCUCUUUGUAUCAAACAGCCUUUUGUUGGGAUGUAGUAUCUCGUUUCUUCCACAUUACGUAAUGUAACAUACAUGAAGUAGAUCAGGAUAUAGCUAAUUUACAACUUUCCUGCAUCGUUCCUGAAUGUUCCUUUUUCAUUUUUUUAAGUGGGAAAAAUGAACACUAUAUUUUAAAUCUUCCUUAUACACUCUAGGCAAUACUUAAACAUUUAACUCUUAGCAAUUUGUGUUUUUAAUGGAAUAGGGUUUUCCUUUUGGGUCAUUUUCGUAGGGUAACUUUGGUUGUCCAAACAUACUCUGAAAUACGUUGGGGAUUAUGGUUUCAACACAUGUAAGCCUAAGGCCAAAGUAUGAGUAACACAUGAUAUUUUGUUACAUUUCAUGAACAAACCACUGUUUUGUGGUAUAAUACAAAACAUAGCUAAGUAGUUUAGAUUACUAUCAGGCAUUACAAGGUUAGGUUUUCAAUUUAUGGGAUUACUCAAAGCUCAUUAGAAGUAUUUUCUCUAGCUCUAGGGAAUGCAGCCUAGAAAAUAGUGGUUUCCCUUGUGAAAACGGUGUGUUUUUAGUCCAUUUAUUAUAUUUUUUAGUUUAUCUCAAUUAUGUCCUUUUGUACUUUAGUACAAUAGUUGAAUUCACAAAUAAGCUUACAAAGUCUGUUUUACCAAUGAGCCAAAAAUGGUAAAAAGAAAAGAGGGAAAACACAUUGUUGUUAUUUAUUAACUUAAACUGUCUUCAGAAUGUCACGGACACUCUGUCAGUGACACUUUUCAGAGCAAACCUACUGUGAUUGGUAGAACAGCUCCGAGUUGUAGUUCUGUCUCUAGCAUACACUACAAUGCCAGUUUGUCUUUCUGAUUUUUUUUGGUUUUCUCAUUUAGAAAAAUGGGCCUAGUAUCCUGUAUUCUGCUAUGUGAAUGUUCUUUCAAGGUAUGCUAGGAAUAACAUGAGCUUUGCAAUUACAUAUAAAUGGGCUCCUAUUCUCUUGCUGUAUGUAUCUGUGAUCUCGAGCACAUUAUUUAACCUCUUUGAGCCCUAGUAUCCUUAUCUGUGAAACAAUGAUAAUGGUAGAGUGUACAUGAUCGGAUUAUUGUGAAGAUUAACUUAGGUUCAUGUAAGUACCAGAGACCAGGAUGGAUGCAGGGUAGCUUCUCACUGCAUGGGAAGUUCUCUCCAUUCUUCCUUACAAUAGAAAUAUGAUUAUCCCAGCACUUUGGGAGGCCGAGGCGGGCGGAUCACGAGGUCAGGAGAUCGAGACCAUCCUGGCUAACACGGUGAAACCCCAUCUCUACUAAAAAUACAAAAAAAUUAGCCGGGCGUGGUGGCGGGCACCUGACGUCCCAGCUACUUGGGAGGCUGAGGCAGGAGAAUGGCAUGAACCUGGGAGGUGGAGCUUACAGUAAGCAGAUUGCACCUGGGCAACAGAGCGAGACUCCAUCUCAAAAAAAAAAAAAAAAGAAAAAGAAAUGUGAUUAUCACUUUAUUCUUUCACACACUGUUUCUUAACUUUUGUUUACAUAUUGGUACUUCAAAAUUGCACUGAAAACUCUUAAAAAAAUAACAGCAAAACAACAAAUGGAUUGUGACUAUAUAGCUGAUACCUGAAGAAUUGGGCCGAAUCCGAUCCAGCACAUGUUUACUGACCUUUUGCUUUGCAUAAUGCAUUGGAGUAACAAAUGAUCUCUUUCUGAGUUCUUGAUAAGUCGACAUUUCAAAACGCUAAGUGAUUUGUUUUUUGAUUUUUUUUAAGCCAAAUCAGAAUGCAUUAUAGGCCAUUACUUUCAAAUUUUCCUUUAUAAUGGAGUAGAGCAAUGUAAGUGUUCAGGCUAUUAGCCACAAAGCUCAAUUCAGUUAGUUAACAUUUAUUGAGCUCUUGGUAUUAUAGGUGCCAUGUGAGGUUCCCAAACCACAAAGCUUGUUCAUCAAAUAAUAAUAAUAACAAUUAUUUCUUUUGGUUUAAAAUGGAAACACUGACCAUAUUUUAAAAACUGAAGUAUUGUCUCGUCUGCAGGACACCACUUCCUUCUGGAGUGGCUUGGGGCCUAAGGGAAAGGGCAGCAGCCAUUGCUCUGGAAGGGAAGUGUGAAGGAAAACCUUCAUGUAGCAUCCGCAUGUAAGUCUUAAGUACACCCACAUUAAGGAAAUAUUUAUACAUGUAAUUUUUGAAUAAUCAUUUACAUCUGGGUCUCUAUCUGCAAUCCCUUUAACUUAAUUCUUGCAAACCUUUUCUCUUCUUGCUUUGACUACCAGGAAGCUUAAAACAGAAUCUGUGGCCCAAUUAUAUUAACUUUGUGAUAUAUUUUUUAGCUUGGGUGUUAUUUUUCUUGGUCCUGAUUUUUGUGGUGUGUCUUUUAUUUUGUUGUCUAUUAGUGAGUGAUAAAAUUUGUUGAGUAGGGAAGAGCAUUAAUAUAAUACAUAAGUCAGAAAAAAAUUCUAGGAAAACAUUUUGCUAGAAGAGAGCUAGUUCUCAAAUGAUUCAGACAUUCGACUUGUAACGCGUAAUGGUUCAACUUACACCUCAUCUGCUCCCCCUUGGAAACUGCAUUUGUUUUGGCAAAGCCAAAAUUGAGUGUUUAGAAAUGGGGUGUUCUGAGAAGAAACCAGCAAAUCCUAGUGAUUCUGGACUGCCCUUGGAAUCCCAGUGCUGGUUUGAACAAUAAUCCUGAUUUUUAACAGCUUAUUAUGUGUGGCUCCACUUUGGGCCAAGGGAAUUUAGUUGUGUUUAAGACUUCGAAUUCCAUCAUGAACUUUGGUCUUGCCUCCUGUCAGUUUAAGAUUAAUUAUGGUAAUUCUCAAAGCAACUGAAUGUGUGUCAGAAUUUCUAUCUGGAUCAGCACUCCUCCUCUGAUCCAGAACCCACGUCUGGGGAGGCUGGGUAAGGAAGUGGAAUUAGGGGAAAGGCAUGCAUUUUAGACAUUUCCCCUGAGUGUGCUUGGUUCUGACUCCAGGCCUUGUCUGCCCACUGUUGACGGUAACUUCUUGUACAUUUGCUGUACAUUUCAUGGUUCACUCAUACAGUUUUUUAGUCAGGGUGCAUCAGAUUUAGUAAUAUGUCUCCAGAAUAACCAUAUGCUUUGAGGUAUAUUUCAUUUUCCAACACUGAAAAUGAAAGAGCUAUUAGGCUAUGAAUCUGUAAACAGUCAGUCGUUCCCUGUGUAAAGUAAAAUGAAUUAUCAUAAUUUAUUAGCAAAUUCAAUUUUCUUUGAAGUGCUAGUUGUAUUUUCAGGCUGCAUCAUAAUGGUUAGUAAUGACUCAUUUAAAAUAAUACCCUAGGAAGUUUUCCAUUUUAGAUUAUUAAUGGUGGGGCAUGAUUGAAAGAGGAACAAAACAUACUGAAUGACUGAAUGUCCUUUCACAAACUUCAGGAAAUAGGGUUACUGGAUCUUCAUGUGGAGUGUUGCUUUUAUUUUAAAUCAAAUGUGAUCUCUACACCAUGUGCCCCAUUUCUUCUCUUGGGUUAAUAAUUCUCUCACAAGAUAUACUGAGUUAGGUAGUAAAAUUGCAUAGUAGUGGUAGUAGUAACAAUAGUACUCCUAGUAAUAGCUAACUCUUUUUGGGUAUCUGCCAAGCUUUCUUCAAAGUACAUUACGUAUAUUAGCUCACUUAAAACUCUUUGUCCUGUGAGUCAAACUUUCUUAUUAUCUCCAUUUUAUAAUCCUAUUAAGGCAGGCAUUUUUAUUAUCCUCAUUUUAUAGGUAAAGAAACUGAGACAUAGACAGGUUAAAGAAGUUACCCAGGGUCACACAGCCAUUGAGUAGAACAGCUGAUAUGAUCUGUGCAGCCUGUAUGCAGAGCUGCUGCUGUAACCACUAUCACAGAGCUGUCUUCUAGUCAUUUUUAUUGUUAAUAUUUUAUAAAUUUAUGUCUCAUUAAAGCACUGUUAAAAACUUUGAUUCCCCCCCCUUUUUUUUUUUACAACAGAUCACUGAUUAGUAACAACAUUCUUAAAUUACAAUAAUGAUCCUCAUAAUGUGUUAUGCAGUUUAUUUCUAUGUUCAUGAUGUCUCUUGUGGCUAGCAUUUAUGGAUAGGCCGUUUUUCAAAGUACUUUAUAUCUGCGAGAACCUUUAGUCCUACUAUUAUUUAGGUAAUAUUAGAUAACAGUCUCUUCUUCAUACGUUGUUGUGAGAAUUAAAUAUGUUCAUCUAUGCAAAGUGCUCUGGAAUAUGUGGCUCAUAGUAAGUGCCCUGGAAUGCUGAUCAUUAUGAUCCAUAUGUUACAGCUGGGGAGGCUGAGACUUUAGUGAGGUUGAAUACUUGCUCGCAGGCCCUUACCCACUUAGAGACAGAGCAAAGCUUUGAACUCGUACACUUGCCCUCUAGAGCCCACACCCAGCCACCACACAAACAAGAAAUAUCAGGACCUUGUCUUUGUUUACUUUGGCAAACCAAAGCUUUUGUUUAGCUUACAAGAAGCAGCAUGGUAUCAAGAUUAAGAGGACAGAGUCUGGAGUCAGCCUUCCUAGAUUGGAAUAGCAUCACCCUCCUUCCUUGAUAGCUGUGCAGCCUUGGGAAAUUUACCUCAACUCUCUGUGCCUUUUCUCAUCUGUAUAGUGGGAAUAAUUACAGCUUGUAUCUCACAGGUUAGCUAUGAAGAUUAAAUGAGAAAAACCUGCAAAACUUAGUACAGUAUCUGGCAUAUGGUAACAUUCAAAUAAUAUUAGCUAACAUGAUUAUUAGAAUUGUAUUUGCAUUUCUUAAAUAUAUUUUGAAUUUUAAAGUCACUGCUUAAAUCCUUGGAGCCACCAGAUGCGGUGGCUCAUGCCUGUAAUCCCAGCACUUUGGGAGGCUGAGGCUGGUGGAUC